UGUAUAUGCUGGAAUGUUUUGUGUUUUCUCCCUUCUAAUUUAAAAAAUUAAUUAUUAAUUUUUAAUAGUAAUGUCUCUAAUUAUGAAGACCUUCAGUAUUUAAGAGGUGAAAGAUUAAUACGAUCUGAAGAGAAACGAGAGUAUGUCUUCGAUAUUUAGAUAAAUAGUUUAGUCUUGGUGUAGCAAAUCAGUUCCAAAAACUAUGUUUCUUGGAAAUCUACAUUUUUCAAAUUUUUUAUGUAUCUUCUAAAAUAAAAAUAAGAUAGGAUGAUGGCUAAGUCUGGGAAUCAUGGAUUAAAAUUGUGCCAACUUCUUAGGGCCUUUUUAAUAUAUUUAAAUUCCAGGAAAUAGUUUAACGUGCAGCAUAUCCAAAUGUACUUGAACACCAUACAGCAUCCAUUAAAAUCUACAGCACUACUUUGGAAAUUCUGUAGUAGUAUUUUACCAUGAACACUAUAGGUAACACUUGUAUAGGAUGAUUUGCAAGGACCAGGAGAAGACUGGUGGCAGGAAAAUCAAAUAAUUGUUAUGGUGAUUUAGGCUUGAAGUUAUGGGGCUAUAGUUCUGACAGUGGAAGAAGGAAGAUCUGAAUGGAUCUGUGAAAUAUUUUGAAGGAAGGUUUUUUGUUUGUUUUGCUUUGGUUUGGUUUUUUUUGGAGACGGGUCUCACUAUGUUGCCUAGGCUGGUAUCGAACUCCUGGGCUCAAGUGACCCUCCCGCCUCAGCCUCCCAAAGUGCUGGGAUUACAGGUGUGAGCCACUGUGCCCUGCCUGAAAGAAGAUUUGAGAAAACUUGGUGAUUUGUUAGAAGGAAGGAGAAAGGAGUCAAAAUAACUCCCAUGUUUCCAGUCUGAGAGAAUUUUGCCAGUCAUUUCAAAUGUGAUAGCUAGGAAGGGCAGCAAGUUGGUUUGACAUUGAAGAGAUUUAGAUGUGUUGACUUGGACCUAGCAGUGGCUGACCGAGGAGCCAAAUACAAAGAAAUUAAAGAAGACCUGGGUCGAGAGAAAUAACUGAAGCCAUGAAAGCAUAUUUCUUCAAUUUCAGUAGAGAGAGGAGCUGCUGGAGGAAAAGGAACCAGAAAAAUGGUACUUAAGAGAUUAUGGCAUCAGAAACCCACAAUGUUAAAAAACGGAACUUUUGUAAUAAGAUUGAGGAUCAUUUCAUUGAUCUUCCUAGAAAAAAGAUCUCUAAUUUCACUAAUAAGAACAUGAAGGAGGUUAAGAAAUCUCCAAAACAGUUGGCUGCUUACAUAAAUAGAACAGUUGGACAAACUGUGAAAAGCCCAGAUAAACUUCGUAAAGUGAUCUAUCGCAGAAAGAAAGUUCAUCAUCCCUUUCCAAAUCCUUGUUACAGAAAAAAACAGUCCCCUGGAAGUGGGGGCUGUGACAUGGCAAAUAAAGAAAAUGAACUGGCUUGUGCAGGCCACCUGCCUGAAAAAUUACACCAUGAUAGUCGAACAUAUUUGGUUAACUCCAGUGAUUCUGGUUCUUCACAGACAGAAAGCCCAUCAUCAAAAUAUAGUGGGUUUUUUUCUGAGGUUUCUCAGGACCAUGAAACAAUGGCCCAAGUUUUGUUCAGCAGGAAUAUGAGAUUGAAUGUAGCUUUAACUUUCUGGAGAAAGAGAAGUAUAAGUGAACUUGUAGCUUAUUUGUUGAGGAUAGAAGAUCUUGGCGUUGUGGUAGAUUGCCUUCCUGUGCUCACCAAUUGUUUACAGGAAGAAAAACAAUAUAUCUCACUUGGCUGCUGUGUUGACUUGUUGCCUCUAGUAAAGUCACUACUUAAAAGCAAAUUUGAAGAAUAUGUUAUAGUUGGUUUAAACUGGCUUCAAGCAGUCAUUAAAAGGUGGUGGUCAGAACUAUCAUCCAAAACAGAAAUUAUAAAUGAUGGAAAUAUUCAAAUUUUAAAACAACAAUUAAGUGGAUUAUGGGAACAGGAAAACCAUCUUACUUUGGUUCCAGGAUAUACUGGUAAUAUAGCUAAGGAUGUAGAUGCUUAUUUAUUACAGUUACAUUGAGAGAUUUCAUCUACUAAAGAGCAUUUGGUUUUUCAAAACAUCCCUGAACUGUAUAAUUUACAAAAAAAAAAAGUCUCGUCUGAGAACUGUGAACUGUGGAAGAAAUCAAAACUAUUUUUUCUUUUAAAAAGCCACGUAAUGAAACCACUAAUGAAAUCCCAGCAAUCUGCUUCACAUUGAAGUGGAAAAAUAUCCAAAAGGAGCAGCUUCAAUUUCAUUGAGGUGAAAGUGCACUAUGAAGAUUGUUCACCUUUGCUGCAUUUGGGAGUUAUAUGGUUAUUUGGUAACAUUAAGAACUACUGGAUUUUAAUGCAAUCCUGCAUAAAAAUAUAAUUUAUACUAUGUGAAAAAAUAAGACAGGACUUACCACUAGGAACCACCAAGACCAAUCAUCAUUAACUUUUUUAAGAUUGUGUUUUAUUAAAAAAAAAAAACACUUAAAUGUGUGCAGCUAUUUUCUUAUGUUGAAAAGACUGAAAGUUUAAAACAUGAAAAAAAUCAAUAUUAAACAUUUUUUGUUCACACUGAGAUACUGUGUAUGUAAAAUGCCUUAAUUAUUAAUAAGCCAAUGUGUUAUGAUACCAAUAUCUGUUUUAAAAAACUAAAACCAACCAUGCUUCUGGCAUGAUAAAAUCAUGGAAUUAAAUCAGGGGUUUACAUUCUUGUAGAGUGUUCUUGAAACACUCUCUGCACCAUUUUUAAAACUUGAGAAUAGUUUUAGUAUCUCUGAUAUUUUUUGCCAGAAUCAUCAUGUCAUGUAUGAAUGUGUUAUCCCUAUCUAAGGAAAAAGGUGAAUAUGUUUUUGUAUGAAUGUUUAACUGGAAAUGUCCAUGGACUUGGCUAAUUUAUAUUUACUUUUUAUUGUACAUAGAUUUCUAAUAUUUUUCAUUCCUGUAUCAUUUAAACUUCCUUCAUUUGAGUAAAUUCACUAAAUAUUUCUAUUUUUUGCUUUUUUAAAUUCUGAUUUUAUAUGAAUUCUAAUUCUUUUUCACUACAUAUGUUUUAAAGAGUUACAUACAGUGAUUUAGAAUGGUUUACAGUUAAUGCUGAUCUUGUAUUUUAAAUUCCAACACUUUGUGUCACUACCUCCUCUAAUGGUUAGUAUGAUAUGCUAGCAGACUGUAUGAGGUCUUUUUUUAAAAUACCACUUUUAGUGUCAGUGAACCAAAUUCUGGAAUGUCUUAACAGCUCUAAAUCUUACUUGUCUUGAAAAUGAUUGGGGUUUAAUACCACUGCUGGUGGUUCACACAUCAUCCCAUCCUUAAUAUGCCUGACAGGCAUCUGAGCAAAGGUUUUUAGUAAUUGAAUUUCUCUGCAGUAGUCCUUCAAGCACUUGAAUGUAAACCUUUAGCAUUUAUUCGUUUAAUGACUACUGAUACGAAUCUCAAGCAGAUUUCUUGCUCUUAAAAGUUAUGUUUCACUGAGUUCUGGUUUUGUGUAGCUAUAUUUUAUAUAGCUAGAUAUUCCUCACAGUGAACAUGAAUUGUAAUAAUUGGUUAUUUCCUUAAGUCUUUAGAUUAUAAUAAUUUCAGAUUAUUGCACGUCUGUGAUUUGAGAGGUGAGUUAUUUAAGAGGCCAGUUUUCAGGACAUGGGAAUUUGAAUUGUAAACCUGUUAUCUCUGUGAAACUUUUAACAUGAUAAAAUAUAACCUUUCUUUGUGCUUA